CGUAAGGCUGGCCUGCUGGUGUGGACAGAGAUUCCAGCAACAUGCAUGACCUGGGGGUACAAGGAUUGCUUCCUAAACAAUGAUAAGCACACAGCCACCUAAUAGUCUGGAUCGGCUGAGACCAUCCUGAUUUCAAACACCCAGUCCCCUUGCCUUCCUAAGAACCCCUGUGUUUCUCAGACUGAAAAUGUGUUUUGAACUUUGUUCACGAAGUGAGGCCGCUGUUGAAAUUCGUCAAGACUGGGAAAGAGCCAAAGUGGGAAGGAGCAUGGGUUGAUUGGCACAAAAGUAGGUCUGCUGAUAAAGAAUGGAAGUAAAGGGGCCAUCAGGUAGAAGCUUUUGCUGUGAGUCAGAAGGACAAUUUAAAAGUUGCCUAAAGAGGCACACGCCAUCUCUGCUGCUGCCUUCCAGUUGGAAGGGAAACUCAGGUUCUUGCCUAAUGGCCGAAGCCCUUCACAGAAUGUCCCCCACCCCUAACAGCUGCCCACUGCCCCUCCCCCUCUGCAGAAUGUCUGGGGUCCUAUGUUCCAGGAACCUGUUUACUUUCAAAUUUUCCUGUUUCAGUUGGACUCAGGAGCAUCUGGUGAGCCAGGUCACUCUCUGGGUCUUACCCUUGGCUUUUCUCAUUGUGGAAACUGCCAGACAGCGGUAGUCAGUGCCCAGCCUGAGGGGAUGGCUUCAAAUGGAGCAUACCCAGCGCUGGGACCGGGCGUGACCGCGAACCCUGGCACCUCCCUGUCUGUGUUCACGGCUCUGCCCUUCACCACACCCGCUCCCGGCCCAGCACACGGGCCGCUCCUUGUGACUGCAGGGGCUCCUCCAGGCGGCCCUCUGGUGCUGUCUAACUUCCCCAGCACACCUCUGGUGACAGAACAGGAUGGCUGCGGCCCGAGUGGGGCCGGGGCUUCCAACGUCUUUGUCCAGAUGAGGACAGAGGUGGGGCCUGUGAAGGCCGCUCAGGCGCAGACCUUGGUCUUAACUCAGACCCCCCUCGUCUGGCAGGCUCCAGGCGCCCUCUGCGGAGGUGUUGUGUGUCCACCUCCCCUACUCCUGGCAGCUGCUCCUGUGGUGCCUGUUAUGGCUGCCCAGGUGGUUGGGGGCACCCAGGCCUGUGAGGGAGGCUGGUCCCAGGGCCUUCCUCUUCCACCACCACCACCACCGGCUGCCCAGCUGCCCCCCAUUGUGUCCCAAGGGAAUGCUGGGCCAUGGCCACAAGGGGCUCACGGAGAGGGCAGCCUGGCUUCCUCCCAGGCCAAGGCCCCGCCAGAUGACUCCUGUAACCCCAGGAGUGUCUAUGAGAACUUCCGACUCUGGCAGCACUACAAGCCCCUGGCCCGGAGGCACCUUCCCCAGAGUCCUGACACCGAAGCGCUUUCGUGCUUCCUCAUCCCAGUUCUCCGAUCCCUGGCCCGGCGGAAGCCCACCAUGACCCUGGAGGAGGGACUGUGGCGGGCCAUGCGGGAAUGGCAGCACACGAGCAACUUUGACCGGAUGAUCUUCUACGAGAUGGCGGAAAAGUUCCUGGAGUUUGAGGCUGAGGAGGAGAUGCAGAUUCAGAAAUCGCAAUGGAUGAAGGGGCCCCAGUGCCUGCCUCCUCCAGCCACACCGAGGCUUGAACCUCGAGGACCCCCGGCCCCUGAGGUGGUCAAGCAGCCAGUGUACCUUCCCAGCAAGGCCGGCCCCAAGGCCCCGACUGCCUGCCUGCCACCACCCAGGCCCCAGAGGCCAGUGACCAAGGCCCGCCGGCCACCACCCCGGCCCCACCGGCGAGCAGAGACCAAGGCCCGCCUGCCACCACCCAGGCCCCAGAGACCAGCAGAGACCAAGGUCCCUGAGGAGAUCCCCCCAGAAGUGGUGCAGGAGUAUGUGGACAUCAUGGAGGAGCUGCUGGGGCCUUCUCUCGGGGCCACGGGGGAGCCCGAGAAACAACGGGAAGAGGGCGAAGUGAAGCAGCCACAGGAAGAGGACUGGACGCCCCCAGACCCGGGCCUCCUGAGCUACACUGACAAGCUGUGUUCCCAGAAAGACUUCGUCACCAAGGUGGAGGCCGUCAUUCAUCCCCAAUUCCUGGAAGAAUUGCUUUCCCCAGAUCCACAGAUGGAUUUCUUGGCCCUAAGCCAGGAGCUGGAGCAGGAGGAAGGACUCACCCUUGCCCAGGGAGCCCCUUCAGAUGCUCCAGGGACUGACAGAUGCUGAGGAAGCCCUGAUCCCUCCCACCACCCACUCACAAGGCCCUGCCUGCUUUAGGGAGGCUUCUUGGGGCCCCCUCAUCGUUAUCAGCAUCCCUGGAAAAUCCUGGGAUUGGAGAGAGCUGGCUGGCUCUUGUUCUGCUCGGUGGGAGCUGAGGAGAAGGCAGCCGCCUGCAACAUGGACAUGGGGAGAGGAGGCUGCUCCUGCUUAACCCUCAUCAGGAAGAGCGCGGGCACUGGGCUGAGGGGAGACGUUGAGGUGACCAUCCACACAGGUGUGUUUGGGAUACGAUGAUGGGUGGGGAGCAGGGGAAGUCCUUCUGCCUGUUUCUGGGCAGGAGAGAGUCUUGUCCAACUAGCUAAAGCAGAUGCUCCUUGCUGUGGCCACAGGGACUGGCCUCGGGGCCCUCAAGGUCCUGCAUGGAGCCCCCCACAGCUAUGAUUCCCUUCCCAUAUGAUGACUGAACUCAUGUGGAAUUGAUGUAGACACAGAUUUACAUUGGUUUCUAAAACAGUUCCCUCCCAACACACCAUCACCAAUGGGAACAAGCAUGUCCAGUCCAUCAGGCGCAGGGUGGGGGUUUCUGCUGGUUCCAGGGCCCGGAGGAGCUGGGGCCCAGGCCAAGAGGGGCCGAGGGUCAGCCGCCCUUCUGCCAGGCACAGACCCCAAGGGCAGAGCAGGGGCUGCCUGGGAUGUGGCAUUGGCUGUCUGGGAAGUGCCCUGGGAGUUGGGGGCUAGGUGUUCGCCAAAGGGAGACUUCCAGAGUCUAUGAGUGAGAUGAGGACUGCAUCAGGAGAGGGACCGAGGCUGGGGAGGAUGCUCUGCUCUUUCCCAGGUUGUCCUGUCUUCCCAAUCUCUGCUGAACUGCCCUCACCCCAUGGGCCAACUCUGCCCCCCUUACCCCUAACCCACCUCUUAGAAUCUCAGAUCCCAGCGUGGACAGGACCCGGCACCCACCCUGGUUCCCUCCUGGCCAACACCUUCUUCUCCACGGUCUGAGUUCUGAUUCCUCCCCCAGGGCGCUUAUUGGCUCAGGACCCCUGUGACUGCCAGGGCACUGGUCCCAGCACUGCCUGCGUGCAGAGCUGUGGUCACGGCCCUGGGGGCUGGCCCAGCAGCAGAGGCUGGUGGGGCAAAGCUGUCUGGUACACGGUGGCCUGGCCCCUCGGCCAAGUGACAAAGGGAGCCAUGUUUGGGUCCUCUCUGGCCCCAUCUGCCCACAGAACACAGCAGUCAGCCUGACAGAUGCCCCUCUGCCCCGUCCCUUCUGCUCGAUGUGGGCAGUGUCGGAGGCCUGCUGUCUUCUGUGGCCUUUGGGAAGGAGAGUUUAUCUUGGCAGGGCUUCCCCAGCUCAGUGCACGUCAGGCCCUCGGGGAAAAUGUGGGGAGCGAAGAGUCACUGGUGGGUGAUGUGGGCAGCUCCCGUGACUCCUCUACAUUCACGGCCAUCCUCAGGAGAUAAGGUAGCACUGCCCCUUUGCAGGGUUUAGGAAUGUUAAGUGAGCCGUGUUUGAAGGGAACAUGGUCCAUACUCUGGCGUGUGUGGGUGCCCAGCCAACUUCCUCACCUAAGGGUGAAAGUGACACCUUGGGGCUCCUGCUGGUUACCCCACUGGCUGUUGUCUAUCCCACUGUCCCUGUCCUUGUCUUGGCUGAGCCAUUCCUAGGAAGCAGAACUUGUGCUUCCUCCACCUCUGUGUCCCACCUGAGCCCUACAAUCUGCCCCUAAAUGGGCACAGUGGGGCUGACUGGGGGGCUCUGGUAGACUGAACAUACGUCCCCCGCCCAGUUCCUGUGCUGAAGCCCUAACCCCCAACGUGAUGGUAUUUGGAAAUGGGGCCUUUGGGAGUUAUUCAGGGUUAGAAGAGACCAUGAGGGUGGGGCCCUAAUGAUGGGAUUAGGGCCCUGGUAAGAAGCAGAGACCCCAGAGCUCUCUCUCUCCCUGACACGAGGACACACUGAGAAGGCGGCCAUCUGCAAGCCAGAGAGAGAGCCCUCACCAGAACCUUGCCCACUGGGAUGCUAACCUCGGACUUCCAGCCUCCAGACUGUGACAAAUACAUUUCUUUUUUUAAUAUGUGCCACCACCCCCAAGUCUAUGGCCCUUUGUCCGAGCAGCCCUAUGUGACUAGGACAAAGUCCAUAAUCUCAAGAACUUCCUUCAUGACUGGUAUCUGGAAACCGUGCAUCAGAGCCACGGGAAAGAAAGGCUCAGCCCUUUACAACUGUCAGCACACCUCCACCCCAAGUGCAGUGUAUCACACAUGAACCAGGAGAGCCUGGGACACAGUGAAAAGGAAUCUGUAAAUACCCAUGAUGUCAUCGCAUCCACACUUGGGGAAGCCAUGCAGCUUGCUCACAGCAGGUGCUGGGGGUGUGCUGAGGCUCUUGGUCGGCUUGGCCUCCCUGCUCACACACCCAGGUCACUCUCUGGGAACCAGUGCGGCUGGGGUGGCCCCUGGCAGGUUUGCCUCCAGAGACCCCUCCCUUCACCAUUGGAUGACAGAUCCCCGAAGAAGCCAUAGCCUCCUGGGAAACUCCAUCUGACAACGUGAGCAAGGCUUGCCCCCGUUAGUGAACAUGCUGUGCUUUCUGACAGCUAUGAGGAUGGACUUGAUCCAGGUGGCUGCCCUUUUGUAGCUCACUUUGAUUCUAACUUCAGCGUUGCAUGAUGCCCUAUGAAUGGAAUAUACAAUGUGUGUCUUUCACAUCUGUCUUCUUUCACUUAGAAUAAUAUUUCCAAUGGCAUCUACAUUUUUAGUAUGUAUCAUUACAUCAAACCUUUUUGUUGCUGAAUAAUAUUCCAUUAAUGGAUAUACUAAAAUUUAUCCAUUUAUCAGUUAAGAACGUUUGGGUUUUUUUCACUUUUUGGCUAUUGUGAAUAACACUUCUAAGAACAUUUGUGUACAAGGUUUCCUGGGGAUGUAUGUUUCCAUUUCUCAUGGCUACAUACCUAAGAGUGAAAUUGGUGGACCAUAUGGAAACUCUGUGUUUAACCAUUUCAGAAGGUGCCAGACUGUUCCCAGUGUACAUGAACCAUUUUAUAUACCCACUAGCUGUGUGAGGGUCCCAGCGUCUCUCCAUAUUCGAGCCAACAUUUAUUAUCAACUCUCUUUUUGAUAAAGUCAUCCUAGUGGUUCUGAAGUUGCAUCUCAUCGUAGUUUGCAUUUGUGUUUCUCUGAUGUUGAACCUCUUUCACGUACCUAUUCGCCACUUGUAUAUCUUCUUUGGAGCAAUGUGUACUCAACAUUUAGUAAUUUUUAACUGGUUUGUGUUUUGUCAUUGAGUUAUAAGAAUUCUUUAUAUAUUCCAGAUAAAAAUGCUUUACAAG